AGUCCCACUCCUUCGACCUCUGCCGCAGCCCGUGCCGCCGCCGCCUCCUGGGAAGAGAGGAAGCGGGAGAGGAGCCCACGUCGCCUGUCACCCAAUAUCUCCAGCCGCGCAGUCCCGAAGAGUGUAAGAUGUUCGCCUGCGCCAAGCUCGCCUGCACCCCCUCUCUGAUCCGAGCUGGAUCCAGAGUUGCAUACAGACCAAUUUCUGCAUCAGUGUUAUCUCGACCAGAGGCUAGUAGGACUGGAGAGGGCUCUACGGUAUUUAAUGGGGCCCAGAAUGGUGUGUCUCAGCUAAUCCAAAGGGAGUUUCAGACCAGUGCAAUCAGCAGAGACAUUGAUACUGCUGCCAAAUUUAUUGGUGCAGGUGCUGCAACAGUAGGAGUGGCUGGUUCUGGUGCUGGUAUUGGAACAGUCUUUGGCAGCCUUAUCAUUGGUUAUGCCAGGUAAUCAUUUCUAUCCCUAAAUAAGUUAAGAGCAUGCUUGCAGUAGUUGGAAACUUAGCUACUGAAAUAAUAGCUACUUUGCAUUAAGUGCUUACUCUGUGUCUUGCAUUAUAUUUAAAGGGCUUUGUAUGCAUUAUCUCACUUAAUUCUCAUAACACCAUUUGGGGUGUUAUGAGAAUAACAUCUAUGAAGGACUAGAGACACAGAGGCCACAUUACUUGCCCAGGUCAUAGCUAGUAAAUGUCAGAAAAUGAAUUUUAACUAAGUCUGACUUCAGAGUCUGCAUUCCUAAUUGUUAAGCUAUUUUGGGAAUAAAAUUAUUAGAGCACAUUCCUUAAAAGGAUCAAUUUAUUUUAUUUAAGACCUAAACUGUCAGAUCUUAAAAGGUAUAGAUCAUAUUUUCAGAUGGAUAAGAAUGUCAGAACCCAUCAAAAUGAAUGAAAACUAACCAUUUAUAUUGACAGACAGCUCCCUACCUUUACACCAUAUUAUCAGGAUUGAAGGAGAAUAGUGUAAGAGAGAUCUAGGCAAAUACUCUUCCAGCAGACUUUUCAGUUUACAAAAAUCCCCACACUAGUAAUCUGAUUCUUUAACAUUUACCAAACAUGUUGAAAUUAAUAUUUCAAAGUAACAGUCAUAUGUGGUCUCUUUUAGAAACCCUUCGCUGAAGCAGCAGCUGUUCUCAUAUGCUAUCCUGGGAUUUGCCUUGUCUGAAGCUAUGGGUCUCUUUUGUUUGAUGGUUGCUUUCUUGAUUUUGUUUGCCAUGUAACAAAUUACUGCUUGACAUGUUGGCAUUCAUAUUAAUUACGGAUGUAAUUCUGUGUAUCUUACUGUGACUCCGAAAACUGUAGUAUUGGUGUCAUGGGAAUGUACGUUAUUUCCAAAGUCAUUUCAUUAAAGAUGAAAACUUUAAUUUCUUCUGUGAUUUGUACUUACACUAAGUUUAGAUUAUCACAAAGAAGAACGUGCAUUCAGGCAGAUGCUGUCCCAUUCAGAGGAAGCUACAGCAGUUGCUCCACUGAUGAAAAAUAUUCCAAUGUAAUUUUUAUGGGAAUUCUUUUAUAUAGUGUUCUGCAUAUUGUAAUUCAUAGGGCUUUUGUUUAUUCAUAUAAAGGAUAAAUAUUUGGGUGUUUUGAGCUUCUAUAAAAUAUGAUUAAUUAAAGGUAGUUAAUACUCAAGAUGGUCUUGAGUUUUUAAGGUCUAACAUCAGUUAGAAUACUUCAAAUCAGAAUCACCUUCCAAGACUGACUUGACAGGUGGUUCUAAAAAUAAAUCACGUCAGCUUUUUAGGAAAUGAAGCCUUAAGCUAGGGGGUAAUGUGACUUUUGUUUUUCAGUAAGUCUCACAUUAAGCAAUUGUGUGCCUCUAAUGAAUCUUCCAUGUCUUUUCAGAACAGGCUCAGUCCAACUAGCAGCUAGUUUCUUACUUGAACAAGACUAUUAAAAACCAAAUAUCAAAAAACUGAAUUGGCUAGAUUUUUACAGCCAAAAAUUGCUGUAAGGCAGUGUGUAUCACUGUUGCUAACAUGUUUAUAGUGGGAGUCUUGGGGAUGAUAGCUGGUUCAACAGUAUUUUGCUGCUAAUACUUUAUGUUGCUUCUUGGUCAAACUUUUCCCAUUCAAAGGAAGAAGAUGGUGCUACUAUAGACAGUUUUUCCCCUAGCAAAUAUAUUGUACCAUAAUAUCUAUCAUCCAAGUUUCAGGGUUUUUUGAAAGUUGAUAAUUAGGAAAGUGACAUUUUACUUUUCUUAGUGCCCUUUGCCUGUUUGAUUUCCAUUGAGAAAGAGCAGUCACCAAAGUUCCUCAAGUGUCGGAAGACCACCUCCAUCAGAAUCAGUGCUUGUUUAAAAAAUAAAAAUCCCUAGGUUCCAGACCUACUGAAUUGGACUCUUUGGACAUGAGACUCAGCAAUCUACAUCUUUAAAAAGGCUUCCCAGGUGGUUUUUGUGCAUACUGUUUGAGAGUCACUAAGUUAUAUAUAUAUCCUACCUUCUGUAAAGUGAAAUGAGGCCCCAAAAAGCUAAAGAGGUAGAGCUGCUACCUCGUUUUUAGUUGAUUCAUCAUCUAGUCUAUAUCACCCAAAAGAAUUGGAAAUAGGUAUUCAAACAAAAACCUGUAUACAAGUAUUCAUAGAAGCACUACUUACAAUAGCCGAAAGGUAGAAACAACCAAAUGUCUAUCAGCUGAUGAAUGGAUAAGUAAAAUACAUCCAUAUAAUGGAAUAUUCAGCCAUGAAAAGGAAUGAGGCACUGAUACAUAAUGAAUAGAUGUGAGUGAACCCUAAGAAAGCAUGCUAAGUGGAAGAAGCCAGCCACAUGAUUCCAUUUAUAUGAAAUAUCCAAAAUAGGCAAAUCCACGGUGACAAAGCCAAUUAGUAGUUAUCAGGAACUAGGGAGGGGGUGAAAAGGGAGUGACUGCGUAAUGCGUAUGGGGAUUCCUUUUAGGAUGAUGAAAAUUGGAUGAAUUACAGCUGGUCUGAUGGUAGUGGGUUAUCAGAACUUAUUAACAUUAGUGUCAUUAAAGUUGGUAUAUAGCCCCUCACUGCUAAAUCUGGCUCAAAAAUUAAAAGAUUAUUAAAAUUUGAUGAAUUAGUGGUGAUGGUUGCACAACAUUGUAAAUAUAAUAAAUGUCACUGAAUUGUACACUUUAAGGUGGUUAAAAUGGCAAAUUUUACAUGUCUUACUGAAACUACUAUUUAAUACAAAGUACAUAGUAUAAAAUUUUAAAAGUGAUAGGAAAAUGCUUAGAUUAAUAUUCACCUAUUCCAAGUAUAUUUUAAAUAAAAACAGUCUUGGUAAAGA